AUAGAGACCGAUGCUGUUCAGCGCGAGAGGGCCUGGAGAGGGUGGGUGUGAGAGAGAAGGUGUCUCAGGUCUCGGGCGCGGGAGGGGGUGGCGGAGAGGACAGGGAGAUUCCCCAGCGCUGGCUCUGAAAUCUGGGGCAGGCUUUCCUUGCCUUACUGCCAAUCCCAACUGUGCCUGGUAGGGUUUGUCCCUGGCGUCAAAGGUAGGAACAGCUGAGCCCUUAGAUGUACCCCUGACGGCGAGAGCCCAGGAGUGGGCGUUUCACUUUUCCUGCGUUUGGGGAGUCCCUGAGGCUAUGCCCUUUGACCUUUGACAUGUGUGCAGCUUCUGCUUCUCCAGAUAAUCUGGUAUUCCAUAUGAAAAAUGAGAUGAGAAACAUCAAGUACAAACCAGUAGACUAUCAACAAUUGCGUGCAUUAACUGAAGCAAAGAAAUUGGCUUCUGCCUCUGCAAAGCUAAAGAUCAGAAAAGCAAUGUUGACUUCAAAGUUAUCCAAAGAACAAACACUAAUAAAACAACACAAGCAAGUGUGGUGGCAGGAAUACCAGAGGCUGAAUGAAGUCAGAUGUAAAAUGGAAUCUGAAAUAAAAUCCCUUCUCAAUGAAGAGAACAUUGGAAAUGAAUGUCUUUGUGACCUUACAAAUUUUGAGCAAGAGCUAUCAGAACAACAGUGCACAUAUCUUAAAAAUGUAAUAAAUCCUAUUCAGCAGCUGAGAGCAGAUCUAAAAUACAGACAGCAUCACACUUUGCAGCAUUCACACCCACAUAUUGAGUUUAACUCCAUGAAAGUAUUGGAAGAGGUUGACUUUGUGAAGAAACAAUUGAAAACUGUCUUUGAAAGACUUAGGCUGGAGCAACAGAGAAUAGAAAAUGAUCUUUCAGACUGGAGUAUAAAGAUUCUAGAUCAUUCUUUGGAAGAAAAGACUAACCCGCUUAGUGAACUGCCCAUUGAAUUAGAAAGUUUGGAAUGCCCAUACCCUGAUUUGAAAUCUUCAAUUCUCAGUGAGUUCUAUAAGUUUACACAGAAAUAUCAGAAGAAGCUUCAAGACUUUAAUCUGCAGUUGGAAGACAUAUACAGAAACUGUCAACUAAGUGAAGAAGACCACUGGAUUUACCAGGCUAUUUUGGAUCAGUACCCUGGAGAUCUCUUUGGAAGAAGGACUCUGUAUCUGGACAUGUUACAAAGAUAUUUUCCUCACAAAUCUAGGCAUGAUUUGGUUGAACACGAGAAAUAUUGUGACCAAUAUCGCUUUGCUAUAGAGCAGCAAAAUAUCCUGAUAUCAAAUUGGAAUAAAAAUAAGAAAGACUUUAUACAGAAGGCUGUGCUGACACUCACUGAGGCUUGUGCAACACAUGAAAUGGAGAGCAUGUUGGCUAAGGACAAGAAAAAGCAACAGGAAUUGUGUGCUGAUCUGAAAGCCAAGGUUCGUCAAUGGCGAGCCCACCAAGAAGAGGUAGCAAGACUGGAAAUGGAAAUUUCUGCCAGAAGAAGAGAAAAGGAAGAGGAGAAAGAGAAACUGUGGAAGAAGAAGGAAUUGUUGCAAAGAGCAGAGAAGAAAAAAAAAAUAAAAAAAUACUGGGCCAAGAAAAAACAGAAGUGGCAAGAAAUGGAAAUGAGAGAUCUUCAGCGUCUAGAAGAACUGAAGAAAUUAAUCGCUGAACAGUCACUAAAAGACAGAGAAAGGGUUAAAUAUAGACAAGAAUUAUUGGAAAGGCGUUUGAUGGAGAAAAAGGAAGUGGCCCUUCAAGAAGCUCAUGAAGACAAAGAGAGAGCACGGCGGCUAGAAGCCCUUAGGAAACAGGUUGCUGUUGUUGCUCAAUUUGAUCCUGUUAGAAUGAUGUCAGAUACAAUGGCAUCAAAAGCUAGAAUGGGCAUUGAAAUUGAAGAAGAAUUUAUUCUUCAAAAGCCACUCUUCACAUUGAAUACAUACAAUGAACAGCAGAUAAUUUCUGACCCUAGACUUCGCUUCGAGUUAGCACUUCGAGAAGCUGGACUUCAUAGAACACUUUAUGCUAAAGAGAUAUUACCAAAAAUUAGUCCUCAAAAACCUCCAAGAAAGGACAUGGAGUCUACUGUAUUUAAAAUAUAGAGCUCAUCCUCAAAUUCUAUAUGUAAAGAGCAUUUUUCUUUGAAAACAUGUAUAUGGAUAAUAAUAAUUACUACUUUCUAAAAUGUUUGAAAUAUCAGACAUAGAAAUCAUAGCAUCUAUUAAAACAACUUUGCCUUUCUUUUGUGAUUCUUAGAAUUUUAUGCACUAUAUUUCCUGUAUCUUUAAGUUAUAUUUAAUAGUACUAAAUUCCCCCAAAUUAUGGAACUUAAUUAUGGCACAUAUAGUACUUAUACUAUAAUUUAGUAAACUACAUGUUGGAGGUUAUGUUAUCCUAUAAAAAGAGCUCAAAAUAACUUUGUGAGAAUUAUAAAUUAUGUAGCUGCUACCUGCUAAUGUUCAUUUCUGCUUGUUAUUUCAGAAUUUGACUUUUUAAUUAUGGAAGCUUCAUUAUCAUUAAUACUUCUAUUAUUUCUUGAUUAUUAUAAGAGGAGACUCAACCUUUCUCUAAAUUUAGAAACCAAUUUGGUACACCAUGUUUACUGCAAACCAAUCAUCCAAACAAUUUCAUUUUGCAAAUUAGCCCUUAAGAAUAAAUUAGAAAUUAGAAAUAGCAUUUCAAGCAUGGGAAUAUCUGUUUUGGUUUGGAAAUAUAUAUAUUUGUGUGAUUGUUUAGAAGAAAUAUUUAAAAUUUCAUAAUAUUUGGAAUGCUGUCAAAAAUUCCAAAUUAUCUAUUAAAUAUUUAGAUGAUUUUAUAGAAAAGGAGCAUUUAAAAUAAAACUCAAACAUAAAUAUUUGACUAUUUCUAAAAAAUAAUUUUUCAAGCAGAAUAACAAGUUAGUGUUGUUGAAAGUUGCCAUUGUUACAGUUAAGAUUACCCCACUCCUUUUUCUGUCUAUUGCAGCUCCCUGACAUUUCCCACCUACCUCCCAGGGGUUGCAGCCUCUGUGCAAUUACUGGAAUAAUGUAAAAAAAAAAAAGCCCAAUCCAACUAGUGGAAUCUUUGACUUUAUGAUUGUCCCCAACAUCAUGGAAAUAAAAAAUACAAGUACAGUCCCGUUAGAAUAAAUCUUCACAAAAGA